AGCCUGUAAUCCCAGCACUUUGGGAGGCCAAGGUGGGCUGAUCACCUGAGUUUGGGAGUUCGAGACCAGCCUAACCAACACGGAGAAACCCCAUCUCUACUAAAAAUACAAAAUUAGCUGGGUGUGAUGGCGCAAGCCUAUAAUCCCAGCUACUUGGGAGGCUGAGGCAGGAGAAUCGCUGGAACCCGGGAGCUGGAGAUUUUGAUGAGCCGAGAUCGUGCCAUUGCACUCCAGCCUGGGCAAUAAGAGCAAAACUCCAUCUCAAAAAAAAAAAAAGAGAGAAAAUACAAAUGGUCGGCCGAGCGUGGUGGCUCAUGCCUGUAAUCCCAGCACUUUGGGAGGCCAAGGCGGGCGGAUCACAAGGUCAGGAGAUCGAGACCAUCCUGGCUAACGGUGAAACCCCGUCUCUCCUAAAAAUACAAAAAAAUUGGCCAGGCAUGGUGGCGGGCGCCUGUAGUCCCAGUUGCUCGGCAGGAGAAUGGCGUGAACCCAGGAGGCAGAGCCUGCAGUGAGCUGAGAUGGCGCCACUGCACUCCAGCCUGGGCAACAGAUCGAGACUCCAUCUCAAAAAAAAAAAAAAGACAAAUCCUCAGACUUGAGGCUGGUAAAGUGCAGGCGCCAAGAAAGAAACUUUCUCUCAAAGCAGUCACUGUUCCUUUGGUCUCUGCUUUCAGAGAGUGGAUUCUGGCUUCCCCCCUUUCCAUGGCAGAGCCUCAGAUAUCAUUGUUUCGUUAUAACAUCUAUGAGGGAAAAAGUGAUUCCUGGCUGGGAGCACCAUGUGUGGAGUGUGCACAUUCUCCCCACGGCCGCCUGCUUUCCUCCACGUCCCAAAGAUGUGUCCAUUAGGUGAAUUGGGGUGUCUCCUUGGUCCCAGCAUGAGCGAGUUUGGGUGUGUGAGUUGCCCUGUGGUGGGACCCUGUCCUAUCCGGGGCUGGUUCUCACCUCGCACCCUGAGCUGCCAGGAUAGGCUCCAGCUACCCAGAACCGUGCAUUAAAAUAAGUGGGUAAAUAAUUAUCUUGUUUUUCUUAAUUUUUUUUUUUAUGGGAGAUUUUCCAGUAAAAACUGAGAAACCUGCUAGACAUUCUAAAAGAGCUGUAGCAAGCACUGUUAAUCUUUCUUUAAGGUAAGGUAUGUAUAACUCACAUUUAUUUCAGUGUUUAAUACUAGAAGUGUUGGAGCUUUUUUUUUAAUUAGAGACAGGGUCUCACUCUGUCACCUAGGUUGGAGUUCCAUGGCAUAGUCAUGGCUUACUACAGCCUCAAACCUCUGGGCUCAAGUGAUCCUCCUGACUUAGCCUCCCAAAUAGCUGGGACCACAGGUAUGCAACAUCACACCCAGCUAAAUAAAAAAUUGUUUUUUAGAGAUGGAGUCUUGCUAUGUUGCCCAGGCUGGUCUUGGACUCCUGGCCUCAAGUAGUCCUCCUGCUUUGGCCACUGGAAAUGCUGGGAUUAUAGGCAUGAGCCACUGUACCUGGCUUAUUACCUUGUAUUGAGUGUAUUAUGUAUGCAUGAUUAGAACAUUCAUUCAUACAGCAGAUAUUGAUGAAAUGUAUUACUUUAUGCCAGAAAUUGUUUGGGUUGCUGAGGAUAAAGAACAGAACAAAGUUCCUGCCCACACAGCACUCACAUACUUGUGGGGGAGACAACAAAACACAUAGUUUGUUGCCUGUGGGGUGUGUGCGUGUGUGUGUGUGUGUGUGUGUGCAUGCAUGUAUAUAUCACAAUUCAUUGAUUCUAAGAUACACUUUCUCCAUAUUUUAAUGUCUCUGAAAUUGAGUUGCCUGUUAGAAUUGAUGGAGUGUUUUUUGUUGUUGUUUGAGACAGGGUUUUGCUCUGUCACCCAGGCUGGAAUGCAGUGGCACAAGCACGGCUCACUGCAGUCUCAACUUCCUGGGCUCAAGUGAUUCUCCUGCCUCAGUCUCCCAUGUAGUUGGAACCACAGAUUCUAAUGUAGGAACUGGUGAGAAGAAGGUGACUGAAGCCUGGAUUUCUGAGGAUGAAAACUCACAUAGGACGACGUCAGACAGACUCACGGUGAUGGAGCUCCCCUCUCCCGAGUCUGAGGAAGUCCACGAGCCCAGAUUAGGGGAGCUCUUGGGAAAUCCAGAAGGUCAGAGCCUGGGGAGUUCCCCCUCUCAGGACAGGGGCUGCAAGCAGGUGACAGUGACCCAUUGGAAGAUCCAGACAGGAGAGACAGCUCAAGUGUGCACCAAGUCAGGAAGAAACCAUAUUCUGAACUCAGACCUUCUUCUGCUUCAGAGAGAGCUCAUAGAGGGGGAAGCCAAUCCUUGCGAUAUCUGUGGCAAAACCUUCACGUUUAAUUCGGACCUAGUUAGGCAUCGGAUUUCGCAUGCUGGGGAGAAACCUUACACGUGCGAUCAGUGUGGGAAAGGCUUUGGCCAGAGCUCACACCUUAUGGAGCAUCAGAGAAUUCACACUGGAGAGAGACUCUACGUCUGUAAUGUGUGUGGGAAAGACUUCAUUCACUAUUCAGGUCUCAUUGAGCAUCAGCGCGUUCAUUCAGGAGAAAAGCCCUUCAAAUGUGCGCAGUGUGGGAAGGCGUUUUGUCACAGUUCAGACCUGAUUAGGCACCAGAGAGUUCACACCAGAGAGAGACCUUUUGAAUGCAAAGAGUGUGGGAAAGGCUUCAGUCAGAGCUCCUUACUUAUUCGCCAUCAGAGGAUUCACACGGGAGAAAGGCCCUAUGAGUGCAAUGAAUGUGGGAAAUCCUUCAUAAGGAGCUCGAGCCUCAUUCGCCAUUAUCAGAUCCACACAGAAGUGAAACAGUAUGAAUGCAAAGAAUGUGGGAAGGCAUUCCGUCAUCGCUCAGACCUUAUUGAACACCAGAGAAUUCACACCGGAGAGAGACCCUUUGAAUGCAAUGAGUGUGGGAAAGCCUUUAUUCGGAGUUCAAAGCUCAUUCAGCAUCAGAGGAUCCAUACUGGGGAGAGGCCUUACGUAUGCAAUGAGUGUGGGAAGCGCUUCAGCCAGACGUCAAACUUCACCCAGCAUCAGAGAAUUCACACUGGAGAGAAACUCUAUGAAUGUAACGAGUGUGGGAAAGCUUUCUUUCUGAGUUCAUACCUUAUUCGACACCAGAAAAUCCACACUGGAGAGAGAGUGUAUGAAUGUAAGGAAUGUGGGAAAGCGUUUCUCCAGAAAGCCCAUCUCACUGAGCACCAGAAGAUCCACUCUGGGGACAGGCCCUUCGAAUGUAAAGACUGUGGGAAAGCCUUCAUCCAGAGCUCCAAGCUGCUUCUGCACCAGAUUAUUCACACUGGAGAAAAGCCCUAUGUGUGCAGUUAUUGUGGGAAAGGCUUUAUUCAGAGGUCAAACUUCCUUCAACACCAGAAAAUUCAUACUGAAGAGAAGCUCUAUGAAUGUAGUCAGUAUGGGAGAGAUUUUAACUCAACUACAAACGUUAAAAAUAAUCAAAGGGUUCACCAAGAGGGACUCUCCUUGAGUAAGGCCCCCAUACAUUUGGGUGAGAGGUCUGUAGAUAAGGGGGAACACACAGGUAACUUAUAAAAUAAUUACUUUCCCGCCCAGUGAGUGAUGUUUGGAAAUGCGUGGAAUUAGGAUUCAUGUGGUUUCUAAGAUUUGGACAUGUCAGAAUUUUGUGAGUCAUGGAUGGGGCUGCUUUUGCAGUGGGUGCCACCUGCCACUGUGCAGCCCUACUCGGCUCAGCCCUUCUCCUCAGCUGUGAGCACUGUCCUCAGGAGAGUCACAGGGCUUGACACCUGACUCUGAGCUGGAACAGUAGGGGCAGGGAGAAGACAGGUCUCAAGAAAAGGUUUUUAAGAAGUUUCAUCCCCAGUUAAGCAGAGUCCAUCCUUGACUUAAAUCCCUUAUUACAGCACAACUGUGUAUCUAAUCUUACGAUUUAGGAGAAUGUUACCUAGGACAUUUUGAUGUGUUAAGUUGAAGAAAGGUAACUCGUGUAUGAACCCCGAGCCAUUUCCCUGUUGUCCUGAGGAGGAACUCCAGGCCUCCCAUCGUGUGCCCUAAGGCCUCCUGCGUCCUGGAGCCCUGCCUCCCACUGCCUGACUUCCUGCCACACGGUUAAUGCUGCAGCAACACCGACUGCUUCAUCUUCCCUGUGCUCCACGUGGCUUCCUACCUCUCUCGCCUUUGUUCUUGUUGAAGGGUCUCUUCUCAGCUAAUUAACUCUGAAUCAUGGUUCAAGACAAGCCUCAGGCAUCAUGUCAAUGGGUGUUUCCCUCAAGCUUAGUUGGCAGCACUCUCCACACUUCUGUGGCUCAGUGAUUACUGCUAUUACUAUAUUUACUUGCAUAUGUCAGAAUGAUGUGAUAGACUAUCUCUGUCACUAUGCUGUUGGGUUCCUGAGGACAGUGAUCAUAUCUGAUUGAUUUCCAUGUGUCCACUGUCUAGCACAGGGCAAUAAAAAAUACACCCCUAAAUCUAUGUGUAAUUGGCAUCUCUCUUGCUUUGUCCUUUCUAUACUGCCAUUCUAAAAAUUUUCAGCUGUUGGCUGUUUUUUUUGUUGUUUGUUCAUUUUGUAUCAGUAUAAUCUACGAUUCUGUUAGAAGUAUCUUCUCAGCCCUGCUACUGUCUGCUGCUCCUACUUAGAAGUUGCAGGCAAUAUCCUGUGCACAUCCACGCCCUCCUGUGUGCCACCUUACAGCUCAUGCAGAACUGUCUACUUGAUCUGGAGGGCAUUGACACCUGGCUCAGCUGGAACAGUGGGGACAGGAGGAGGCAGGUCUCAAGAGAAGGUCUUUACUUACUUGUCUGUAUCUUUCUGUCUCACUCGAAAGGCACAGUCUCAAUGCGCUACGUAACUCUUCUGUUGUAGCAGUUCUGAGGUUGAACUGAGCUCUUGUCAUUUUCCAUGCUCUCUGGCUCAUUGUGUCAUUUCAAAAUGUAUUGAUAUCUAUAAGGAAUAGUCCUCAAUGUUGGGAAAACAGAUGAGCAACCCACUACCCUGAAGUCAUCCACCGUGUAGUGGGGAAGACGGAGAUCACAGUAGGGUGAGUUAAGUAUGUGCCCUCAGGUGUGAAGGAGCACAGGUGAGGGGGUGCCUGCUGUGGCACAGAGCUGGGAAGGCCUUACAGAAGAGGUGACAUUUCAGCUGGGCCAGAGAUCAGUAGAGAGCAGCUGAAGAAGAAAAUAGGGUCCAGGAGAGGAAUCUGCAGAAACAUGGAGCCAUGACAGAUGGCUUUUUGGCUAGGACUGUUCGAAAGCAGGCGAGGUAAAUGGACAGUGGACAGCCGCCUCGCCAAACUGUUAGUCUUUACCUCUGAAUUUCAUCUGGACAUGAACCCCAAAGUCCAGUUUUGUAACGAUAUAAUUUUUUUCUCAUGAGGCCAUAUUUUGAGUUCUUAAAUACUACCAACCCUGAACGUCUCAGGACAAAUAAUUCAAAAAAGAGAUCUACAUUUUCUGGAAAAUCAGCAUUACUAGAGAUGUUUCAAAUGUAGAUUUUACCAGACCAUUUUAAUCAACUUUAUUGAGAUUCAAUUUUCAUAUAGUAAAACGCCUAUUUAAGUGUACAAGGUUUUGAAAAAUCUAUACACCUGUGUAACCACCACCACCUGUGUAACCACCACCGCCAGAACCAAAAACGUUUCUGUCACCCAAAGAAGUUCCCUUUUGCCUUUUCCUAGUUAAGCCCACUCCAGCCCCAGAUAACCACUUUCUAUCCUCAUAGAUUAGUGUUGCUUGGUUUAGAGCCUCAUACAAAUGGAUUCAUUUACUAUGUGUUCUUUUGCGUCUGAUGUCUCACUUUGGCAUGUUUUUAGACUCAUCCAAGCU